GUAGUUGAUCUCCGGAGUUUCGCCAUGCGGAACUUGGGGGCUUUCGCGGCCCGCGUCGGUGCGGAGUAGCUGCUUUAGCCCCGACCAAACCGUCCUCUACAGCCUCCUGGCCCCGGCGCAGGCUGCCCGUACUGCCCGUGGCAUGAGGGAGCCGGAAGAGCUGAUGCCCGAUUCGGGUGCUGUGUUUACAUUUGGGAAAAGUAAAUUUGCUGAAAAUAAUCCCGGUAAAUUCUGGUUUAAAAAUGAUGUCCCUGUACAUCUUUCAUGUGGAGAUGAACAUUCUGCUGUUGUUACCGGAAAUAAUAAACUUUACAUGUUUGGCAGUAACAACUGGGGUCAGUUAGGAUUAGGAUCAAAGUCAGCCAUCAGCAAGCCAACAUGUGUCAAAGCUCUAAAACCUGAAAAAGUGAAAUUAGCUGCCUGUGGAAGGAACCACACCCUGGUGUCAACAGAAGGAGGCAAUGUAUAUGCAACUGGUGGAAAUAAUGAAGGACAGUUGGGGCUUGGUGACACCGAAGAAAGAAACACUUUUCAUGUAAUUAGCUUUUUUACAUCCGAGCAUAAGAUUAAGCAGCUGUCUGCUGGAUCUAAUACUUCAGCUGCCCUAACUGAGGAUGGAAGACUUUUUAUGUGGGGUGACAAUUCCGAAGGGCAAAUUGGUUUAAAAAAUGUAAGUAAUGUCUGUGUCCCUCAGCAAGUGACCAUUGGGAAACCUGUCUCCUGGAUCUCUUGUGGAUAUUACCAUUCAGCUUUUGUAACAACAGAUGGUGAGCUAUAUGUGUUUGGAGAACCUGAGAAUGGGAAGUUAGGUCUUCCCAAUCAGCUCCUGGGCAAUCACAGAACACCCCAGCUGGUGUCUGAAAUUCCGGAGAAGGUGAUCCAAGUAGCCUGUGGUGGAGAGCAUACUGUGGUUCUCACGGAGAAUGCUGUGUAUACCUUUGGGCUGGGACAAUUUGGUCAGCUGGGUCUUGGCACUUUUCUUUUUGAAACUUCAGAACCCAAAGUCAUUGAGAAUAUUAGGGAUCAAACAAUAAGUUAUAUUUCUUGUGGAGAAAAUCACACAGCUUUGAUAACAGAUAUCGGCCUUAUGUAUACUUUUGGAGAUGGUCGCCACGGAAAAUUAGGACUUGGACUGGAGAAUUUUACCAAUCACUUCAUUCCUACUUUGUGCUCUAAUUUUUUGAGGUUUAUAGUUAAAUUGGUUGCUUGUGGUGGAUGUCACAUGGUAGUUUUUGCUGCUCCUCAUCGUGGUGUGGCAAAAGAAAUUGAAUUCGAUGAAAUAAAUGAUACUUGCUUAUCUGUGGCGACUUUUCUGCCGUAUAGCAGUUUAACCUCAGGAAAUGUACUGCAGAGGACUCUAUCAGCACGUAUGCGGCGAAGAGAGAGGGAGAGGUCUCCAGAUUCUUUUUCAAUGAGGAGAACACUACCUCCAAUAGAAGGGACUCUUGGCCUUUCUGCUUGUUUUCUCCCCAAUUCAGUCUUUCCACGAUGUUCUGAGAGAAACCUCCAAGAGAGUGUCUUAUCUGAACAGGACCUCAUGCAGCCAGAGGAACCAGAUUAUUUGCUAGAUGAAAUGACCAAAGAAGCAGAGAUAGAUAAUUCUUCAACUGUAGAAAGCCUUGGAGAAACUACUGAUAUCUUAAACAUGACACACAUCAUGAGCCUGAAUUCCAAUGAAAAGUCAUUAAAAUUAUCACCAGUUCAGAAACAAAAGAAACAACAAACAAUUGGGGAACUGACGCAGGAUACAGCUCUUACUGAAAACGAUGAUAGUGAUGAAUAUGAAGAAAUGUCAGAAAUGAAAGAAGGGAAAGCAUGUAAACAACAUGUGUCACAAGGGAUUUUCAUGACGCAGCCAGCUACGACUAUCGAAGCAUUUUCAGAUGAGGAAGUAGAGAUCCCAGAGGAGAAGGAAGGAGCAGAGGAUUCAAAAGGAAAUGGAAUAGAGGAGCAAGAGGUAGAAGCAAAUGAGGAAAAUGUGAAGGUGCAUGGAGGAAGAAAGGAGAAAACAGAGAUCCUAUCAGAUGACCUUACAGACAAAGCAGAGGUGAGUGAAGGCAAGGCAAAAUCAGUGGGAGAAGCAGAGGAUGGGCCUGAAGGUAGAGGGGAUGGAACCUGUGAGGAAGGUAGUUCAGGAGCAGAACACUGGCAAGAUGAGGAGAGGGAGAAGGGGGAGAAAGACAAGGGUAGAGGAGAAAUGGAGAGGCCAGGAGAGGGAGAGAAGGAACUAGCAGAGAAGGAAGAAUGGAAGAAGAGGGAUGGGGAAGAGCAGGAGCAAAAGGAGAGGGAGCAGGGCCAUCAGAAGGAAAGAAACCAAGAGAUGGAGGAGGGAGGGGAGGAGGAGCAUGGAGAAGGAGAAGAAGAGGAGGGAGACAGAGAAGAGGAAGAAGAGAAGGAGGGAGAAGGGAAAGAGGAAGGAGAAGGGGAAGAAGUGGAGGGAGAACGUGAAAAGGAGGAAGGAGAGAGGAAAAAGGAGGAAAGAGCGGGGAAGGAGGAGAAAGGAGAGGAAGAAGGAGACCAAGGAGAGGGGGAAGAGGAGGAAACAGAGGGGAGAGGGGAGGAAAAAGAGGAGGGAGGGGAAGUAGAGGGAGGGGAAGUAGAGGAGGGGAAAGGAGAGAGGGAAGAGGAAGAGGAGGAGGGUGAGGGGGAAGAGGAGGAAGGGGAGGGGGAAGAGGAGGAAGGGGAGGGGGAAGAGGAGGAAGGAGAAGGGAAAGGGGAGGAAGAAGGGGAAGAAGGAGAAGGGGAGGAAGAAGGGGAGGAAGGAGAAGGGGAGGGGGAAGAGGAGGAAGGAGAAGGGGAGGGAGAAGAGGAAGGAGAAGGGGAGGGAGAAGAGGAGGAAGGAGAAGGGGAGGGAGAAGAGGAAGGAGAAGGGGAGGGAGAAGAGGAGGAAGGAGAAGGGAAAGGGGAGGAGGAAGGAGAGGAAGGAGAAGGGGAGGGGGAAGAGGAGGAAGGAGAAGGGGAAGGGGAGGAUGGAGAAGGGGAGGGGGAAGAGGAGGAAGGAGAAUGGGAGGGGGAAGAGGAGGAAGGAGAAGGGGAGGGGGAAGAGGAAGGAGAAGGGGAAGGGGAGGAAGGAGAAGGGGAGGGGGAAGAGGAGGAAGGAGAAGGGGAGGGGGAAGAGGAGGAAGGGGAAGAAGAAGGGGAGGAAGAAGGAGAGGGAGAGGAAGAAGGGGAGGGAGAAGGGGAGGAAGAAGAGGAAGGGGAAGUGGAAGGGGAGGUGGAAGGGGAGGAAGGAGAGGGGGAAGGAGAGGAAGAGGAAGGAGAGGAGGAAGGAGAAGAAAGGGAAAAGGAGGGGGAAGGAGAAGAAAACAGGAGGAACAGAGAAGAGGAGGAGGAAGAAGAGGGGAAGUAUCAGGAGACAGGCGAAGAAGAGAAUGAAAGGCAGGAUGGAGAGGAGUACAAAAAAGUGAGCAAAAUAAAAGGAUCUGUGAAAUAUGGCAAACAUAAAACAUAUCAAAAAAAGUCAGUUACUAACACACAGGGAAAUGGGAAAGAGCAGAGGUCCAAAAUGCCAGUCCAGUCAAAACGACUUUUAAAAAACGGGCCAUCAGGUUCCAAAAAGUUCUGGAAUAAUGUAUUACCACAUUACUUGGAAUUGAAGUAACAAACCUUAAAUGUGACCCGAUUAUGGCCAGUCAGACAAUUUAAAUGCCUUGCAUAUAACGGGCACUCAUUACGUGUUAUUAAAUUGAUUUUAUGUCAAUUAUUUUAUGUGUAGUAAAAAAAAAAGCAACUGAUGCAGCUGUGUUAAGGAGCCAAAGACAAUAGGAGGCACUGGUAAAUUUUGGCCUCUCUCAAACUAAAAUUUUCGUGUAUUUCCCCCCCAAAUUAUAAAAACAUAACUAGAAAAUAUUAAAAGGUCAUAUCAGAUUAUUAACAUUAUAUAUUCAUUAAAGGCAGCUUUAGGAAACAGGAAUAUACUACAAGAGUGUUUUGUUUGUGUAUACAAAUCAUUCCAUUUUUAAAUGGCACAGAUGCUUAAGGGCUAUAAAAACUUCUAAUUUCUUAUAAAUAUGUUAGCACUUUUUUUAAGUUAGUGAUUACAGUUUACCUACUGUAUAGAAUAAUUUUCUAAUAAUGGAUGGUAUUCUAAAACUCAAUUGAGGCAUUCACAUUUUAAAGAAAGUAUUGUCUUUCACCUUUUAUGUGUUCUUUUUGCAAAAAUCUACAAAGUGACAGCUGUGUUCAGAGCUUAGAUCCCAAAAACGUGAUCUCUUUUAGUUACUAUCUGGGCAGAUGGUAGUAUAUCUAAUGAAAUGGUGAUUAAUUUAAAUGUAUAAUCUGGAAAUAUGUAAAACUUGAAGUAUUUUUUGUCCAGGCAAAGGUACUCAUUGGGCCUCAGUUUCUUCAUCUCUAAAAUGGAGUGGAUGAGAUGAUGUGAUAACUGCAGUCCCUUCUAACUCUUAAAUUCUUUUCAUUCUCACAGAUUCACUCUAUCAUUAUUGUUAUUCAUGUAAGAAACGUUUUAGGGAGAAAAAUUACACUUUAAAAUUAAUUUAGUUUUCUAUACAGUUGUUUUCUUUACUCUUGAAAAGUUAUGACAGCUUUAACGUCUCUUGUCUUCUGUAAUUUUUUAUUUCUAAACUCCUAUCAUUUCCAAGCUUUAACUGUACUUUAUCAGAGCCUUCAUUUCUGGUAUGUGUUAUAUGCCCUCAAUGUAUUCACUGACUGUUCUGUAAUUUCAGUUUGUCUGUUCCUUGUCAGAAUGUUUCAAGUAAAAUAAAAAAUUAAAUGUA